AGAAAUCUCCUCAAGCCAGAGCCUGUGCUGUGAGGGGCUUCGGGACCUUGGGGCAGCUCCUGAGUUCAGACAGAGUUCAGGAAGGGAGACAGGGGCACAGAGAGACAGAGGUUCAUGGACUGAGGCAAAGGCUGGGCCAGGCUCAGCAACCCAGGCCUCCCGCAGGCAGGCAGAGGCUGCCCUGUAACCCAUGGAGACCAGACCAACAGCUCUGAUGAGCUCCACAGUGGCUGCAGCUGCGCCUGCAGCUGGGGCUGCCUCCAGGAAGGAGUCUCCAGGCAGAUGGGGCCUGGGGGAGGAUCCCACAGGCGUGAGCCCCUCGCUCCAGUGCCGCGUGUGCGGAGACAGCAGCAGCGGGAAGCACUAUGGCAUCUAUGCCUGCAACGGCUGCAGCGGCUUCUUCAAGAGGAGCGUACGGCGGAGGCUCAUCUACAGGUGCCAGGUGGGGGCAGGGAUGUGCCCCGUGGACAAGGCCCACCGCAACCAGUGCCAGGCCUGCCGGCUGAAGAAGUGCCUGCAGGCGGGGAUGAACCAGGACGCCGUGCAGAACGAGCGCCAGCCGCGAAGCACAGCCCAGGUCCACCUGGACAGCAUGGAGUCCAACACUGAGUCCCGGCCGGAGUCCCUGGUGGCUCCCCCGGCCCCGGCAGGGCGCAGCCCACGGGGCCCCACACCCAUGUCUGCAGCCAGAGCCCUGGGCCACCACUUCAUGGCCAGCCUUAUAACAGCUGAAACCUGUGCUAAGCUGGAGCCAGAGGAUGCUGAUGAGAAUAUUGAUGUCACCAGCAAUGACCCUGAGUUCCCCUCCUCUCCAUACUCCUCUUCCUCCCCCUGCGGCCUGGACAGCAUCCAUGAGACCUCGGCUCGCCUACUCUUCAUGGCCGUCAAGUGGGCCAAGAACCUGCCUGUGUUCUCCAGCCUGCCCUUCCGGGAUCAGGUGAUCCUGCUGGAAGAGGCGUGGAGUGAACUCUUUCUCCUCGGGGCCAUCCAGUGGUCUCUGCCUCUGGACAGCUGUCCUCUGCUGGCACCGCCCGAGGCCUCUGCUGCCGGUGGUGCCCAGGGCCGGCUCACGCUGGCCAGCAUGGAGACGCGUGUCCUGCAGGAAACUAUCUCUCGGUUCCGGGCAUUGGCGGUGGACCCCACGGAGUUUGCCUGCAUGAAGGCCUUGGUCCUCUUCAAGCCAGAGACGCGGGGCCUGAAGGAUCCUGAGCACGUAGAGGCCUUGCAGGACCAGUCCCAAGUGAUGCUGAGCCAGCACAGCAAGGCCCACCACCCCAGCCAGCCCGUGAGGUGACCUGAGCAUGCGCCCACCCACUCAUCUGUCCCUGACCUCUAACCUUUCUCUGCCUCUCCCACACUCUCCCAGAGCUCACUGAUUAGACAGCACAAGGGUCUCAGUUCAACAGCAUACAGCCAACAUCUAUGGUGUCCCAGGCACAGUGCCAGGCCCCGGGAGUGGGGACCAAGAUGUACAUAAGACAAAGCUACUGCCUUCUAGAGACAACCGGCAGUGACCUCACUGAAGACAAAAACUGCCCUAGCCAGGUACUGAGGGUUGCAUGAAUCUGCAGGAGACAGAGAUCCCCUUGCAUGGGAAACAUAAAGCAGAAUUGGGAGGGACUUUGUGGAGACAGGGCUGGACUUGAAAGGAAGAAGAAGUCUAAAAGAAAACAUCAUUUGCAAAGGGAGAGAGGGGCAAGCAUGAUAUGUUGUUAGAACAGGAGCCCACUUUGAAGGUAUAACAGGUUCCUGCCAGUGAGAAAUGGGGAGAAUAAGCCAGAAAAGUACCCUAGGACCAGCCCGUUCAGGACUUUGAAUGCCAGCCAAAGGCCACGUCUGACUUGGGAGGCAGAGGGCAGCUACUGCAGGUUUCCGAGCAGAGGGUCAUACACAGGGCUGGACCUCACGCAGACUGGCAUGGCCAUGGGUCCAGAGGAUACUACUGGGAAGGGGAUGGCAGCUACUGCCACCUUCCAGAUGGUUCCAUGGAGUUCUGAUCUUUGGGCAUGGCCAGGGGAAGCAGAAGGGAGACUCUAGGAGUUGAAAUGGGUCAGACCCGGUGUUUGGGUGAAGGUAAGGAAUGAGGGAAGAGGAGCUCUUUG